GUCCUUCUAAUCCUAGUCUUCGUUUGGUCCGGUUGCACUCUUCCUAUAGCCCAGAGGGCGAGAGGGCCUGUGGCCUGGGGGAAGGAGGACGAGGUUCUGCCUGGAUCCCAGCAGUAGGACGCUGUGCCAUUUGGGAACAAAGGAAUAGUCUGCCUGGAAUCCCUGCAGAUCUUGGGGCCGGAGGCCAGUCCAACCCUUGGAGCAGGAAGAAACGCAAAGUUGUCAAGAACCAAGUCGAGCUGCCUCAGAGCCGGCCCGCAGUAGCUGCAGACUCCGCCCGCGACGUGUGCGCGCUUCUCUGGGCCAGAGCGAGCCUGUUUUGUGCUCGGGUUAAGAGAUUUGUCCCAGCUAUACCAUGGGCCGCACUCGGGAAGCUGGCUGCGUGGCCGCUGGUGUGGUUAUCGGGGCUGGUGCCUGCUACUGUGUAUACAGACUGGCUUGGGGAAGAGACGAGAACGAGAAAAUCUGGGACGAAGACGAGGAGUCUACGGACACCUCAGAGAUUGGGGUUGAGACUGUGAAAGGAGCUAAAACUAACGCUGGGGCAGGGUCUGGGGCCAAACUUCAGGGUGAUUCAGAGGUCAAGCCUGAGGUGAGUUUGGGACUCGAGGAUUGUCCGGGUGUAAAAGAGAAGGCCCAUUCAGGAUCCCACAGCGGAGGUGGCCUAGAGGCCAAGGCCAAGGCCCUUUUCAACACGCUGAAGGAACAGGCAAGUGCAAAGGCAGGCAAAGGGGCUAGGGUGGGUACCAUCUCUGGGAACAGGACCCUUGCACCGAGUUUACCCUGCCCAGGAGGCAGGGGUGGAGGCUGCCACCCCACCAGGAGUGGAUCUAGGGCCGGGGGCAGGGCAAGUGGAAAAUCCAAGGGAAAGGCCCGAAGUAAGAGCACCAGGGCUCCAGCUACAACAUGGCCUGUCCGGAGAGGCAAGUUCAACUUUCCUUAUAAAAUUGAUGAUAUUCUGAGUGCUCCCGACCUCCAAAAGGUCCUCAACAUCCUGGAGCGAACAAAUGAUCCUUUUAUUCAAGAAGUAGCCUUGGUCACUCUGGGUAACAAUGCAGCAUAUUCAUUUAACCAGAAUGCCAUACGUGAAUUGGGUGGUGUCCCAAUUAUUGCAAAACUGAUAAAAACAAAAGACCCCAUAAUUAGGGAAAAGACUUACAAUGCCCUUAAUAACUUGAGUGUGAACGCAGAAAAUCAGGGCAAGAUUAAGACGUACAUCAGUCAAGUGUGUGAUGACACCAUGGUCUGUCGCUUGGACUCAGCUGUGCAGAUGGCUGGGCUAAGACUGUUAACCAACAUGACUGUGACUAAUCAUUACCAACAUUUGCUUUCCUAUUCUUUUCCAGACUUUUUUGCUUUGUUAUUCCUGGGAAAUCACUUCACCAAGAUACAGAUUAUGAAACUAAUUAUAAACUUUACUGAAAAUCCAGCCAUGACAAGAGAGCUGGUCAGUUGUAAAGUACCAUCAGAAUUGAUUUCCCUCUUUAAUAAAGAAUGGGAUAGAGAGAUUCUUCUUAAUAUCCUUACCCUAUUUGAGAAUAUAAAUGACAACAUAAAAAAUGAAGGGCUCGCAUCAUCCAGGAAAGAAUUCAGCAGAAGUUCACUUUUUUUCUUAUUCAAAGAGUCUGGAGUUUGUGUUAAGAAAAUCAAAGCACUAGCAAAUCACAAUGAUCUGGUGGUGAAAGUAAAAGUCCUGAAAGUAUUAACCAAACUCUAAUUUGGAGUCUGUCCCAAACAAUAUUGAGAUAUUUGCAGUUGGUACGAUGUGAUUUGUAAAUUCUUUGUUUUUCAUUGUGCGUAUAUGGUAAAGAGAUCUUUUCAGCUGCUAUUUUGGAAUAAUGACUAUCAUAUAUCAUAACAGUGACUGAUGUUGGUUGUAAUGGUUGGGUUUAGGAUGAACCAUUUUAAGGAUGCCAAAUGAAAUAUUAGUAUUUGUACACAGAAAGAAUUUAUUGAUUUGAUCUUAUUACCUAGAUUGAGAUUUUUUAAUCUUUCCUCUACCUAAACUGACAAUGAAUUGGUUAUACAUCAUGCAUAAGCUACACUUUUAUAUUAGUUUAUAUUUGUUAUUCUAAGACUUGUGUUUCAUCAAUAAAGUUGUGUUUUAAGCAGCAGAAAAAAAAAA